UCCAGUGAGUUGCAAGCUUAAUGCUCACCUGCAGAGACAGAAUUCCUGAGUGAACGAACAGAGCAGCUCCUCUUCCAUCUCCAGGGUCUCAUUCUGUUGCCCAGGCUGGAGUGCAGUGGUGCGAUCUCGGCUCACAGCAACCUCUCUGCCUCCAGGUUCAAGCCAUCCUCCCAACUAAGCCUCCCGAGUAGCUGGGACUAAAGAUGUGUACCACCAUGUAUUUUGGCUGUUUGAACUGGGGAACAAAGCCUGCUGGAUUUAAUGGACUCCAACUUCAAAUGAUUGCUGCUAAUGAUAUUCUAGAAAUCCAUAGGCCUUCAUUUCUUCUGUGUCUAUCCACCAGAGGGGUCUGAUCUCUAGAUUUUUUCAGGAGGCAGAAGAUGAGGUGGGGUUAAAGAAGUAGGAAAGAGUAUCCUUAAAUACAAAGAUCCUUCCUAAUUAGGCCCUGUGUUCCAGAGUCCCAGGCAUCCUUGUCAUGGAGCAAUGACAGAGUCUUGCGAAAGAGACAUACCCCAGCUCUGAAUUAGGGGACAGAGUAACACCAGGAUGUGGACUAGACAGAACAAGGCCUGGAGGUGGACCAGAGCCCAGCUCCCUUGGCUCCUAGAUGAAUCAUCUUUCUGCAAGAUGGCAAAGGAAACAAAUAGUUUUAGGUUCCCAUGUAAGACCAGGCUUUUGAGGUUUAGGUCUGCUUUCCCCAUUGGUGCAGCUGGGGGCGUUAAAUAUUUAAUCAGUUUGGCCUGGGUACAUGCAGAUCGAUGGCCAUAGCAUUAAUCCAUUAAUGGCUGUGUGGUGGGGAGUACACAGUGGCAGAAGGCAGUUGGGGGCUUGCAGCAGUAGCUGUUUCCCCACCAGUAUGGUAGCAUUUCACUAUUGGUAUAAAGUGGCUCUAAUUUUCUGGCUUCAACCAGACAAAAAAGAAACUGACCUUGAAUGCUUGAGCCUUCAAAGCCAUAGAUGCAGAUCUGAGCGAUUACCAUCUGGCUGUUUGAAAACUUCAAACAAAAAAGUCAACUUGAGAUUCUGCCAAGAAACAGUGAUUUGUGUUUCUUUGUAUGUCAGGCUCACAGGUCUCCAGUGAGACAUAGGAAAACCUUUGCCUCUUCCCCUCUCUCCAAACACAGGGCUGGUUCUCCUAGUGAGGAGGUUUCACUUUCUAUCCUUGGCCUACAAACAAAGAGAUUAAGAGUUUGUGGUUGACACUGCAGGGCGUGAGAUUGUUGAGUCUUGGGUGUGAGUGCCUUAGAAAUGAGCAUUCAUAUGCUGAUCACAAACAGCCUCAUCUCUUGAUGAAAACAUAGUAUCUGUUGGCCUUAUUCUGAUUAUAAGGACAUAUUUUAAAUUUUGUAGGAUUUGAAUGAGGUUCUCCAAUAAUUACUCCCAACUUUAAGAGGGCUUUGCAUGUUUUGUUUGACAUUGUUUUAUUUUCUUCACAGCAAAUAUCAUUAUCUGAAAUGAUCCUAUUCAUUUAUGUAAUUACUGUCUGAUCCUCCCAGUAAAGUACAUUGAGACCUCGUCUUUCUUUUCUGAUUUUUUUUCUUUUGGGGUCUUUUGGCCCUAUGAAAUGGAAAGGUGUAGGGAUCUACAGGUGAGCUUGGACAUAGAUGUGAACUCAAGCUGAAACUGAACUGAUGCUCGCAGGUUGGGAUCAGCAGAAAGAGGAGUGAAAGAGUGGUGUUUUCCUGGCAGCUGGUCAUGGCUUUUGAUAAGGCAGAGCUGCCUAGCUCUCCCAAGGUGCUGGUGUUGACCACUGAAAUGACCUCCACCUUCAACCCCCGAGAAUGUAAACUGUCCAAGCAAGAAGGGCAAAACUAUGGCUUCUUCCUGCGAAUUGAGAAGGACACCGAGGGCCACCUGGUCCGGGUGGUUGAGAAGUGUAGCCCAGCAGAGAAGGCUGGCCUUCAAGAUGGAGACAGAGUUCUUAGGAUCAAUGGUGUCUUUGUGGACAAAGAAGAACAUAUGCAGGUUGUGGAUCUGGUCAGAAAGAGUGGGAAUUCAGUGACUUUACUAGUUCUGGAUGGGGAUUCCUAUGAGAAAGCAGUGAAAACACGGGUGGACUUGAAAGAGUUGGGUCAAAGUCAGAAGGAGCAAGGUUUGAGUGAUAAUAUACUUUCCCCUGUGAUGAAUGGAGGUGUGCAAACUUGGACCCAGCCCCGGCUCUGCUAUCUCGUGAAGGAAGGAGGCAGCUAUGGCUUCUCUCUGAAAACUGUCCAAGGUAAAAAGGGGGUGUACAUGACUGAUAUUACACCUCAAGGUGUGGCUAUGAGAGCUGGAGUUCUGGCUGAUGAUCACUUGAUUGAAGUGAAUGGAGAGAAUGUAGAGGAUGCCAGCCAUGAGGAAGUGGUUGAAAAGGUGAAGAAGUCAGGAAGCCGUGUCAUGUUCCUGCUGGUGGACAAAGAAACUGACAAGCGUCAUGUUGAGCAGAAGAUACAAUUCAAAAGAGAAACAGCCAGUUUGAAACUGUUACCCCACCAGCCCCGAAUUGUGGAGAUGAAGAAAGGAAGCAAUGGCUAUGGUUUCUAUCUGAGGGCAGGCUCAGAACAGAAAGGUCAAAUCAUCAAGGACAUAGAUUCUGGAAGUCCAGCAGAGGAGGCUGGCUUGAAGAACAAUGAUCUGGUAGUUGCUGUCAACGGCGAGUCUGUGGAAACCCUGGAUCAUGACAGUGUGGUAGAAAUGAUUAGAAAGGGUGGAGAUCAGACUUCACUGUUGGUGGUAGACAAAGAGACGGACAACAUGUACAGACUGGCUCAUUUUUCUCCAUUUCUCUACUAUCAAAGUCAAGAACUGCCCAAUGGCUCUGUCAAGGAGGCUCCAGCUCCUACUCCCACUUCUCUGGAAGUCUCAAGUCCACCAGAUACUACAGAGGAAGUAGAUCAUAAGCCUAAACUCUGCAGGCUGGCUAAAGGUGAAAAUGGCUAUGGCUUUCACUUAAAUGCGAUUCGGGGUCUGCCAGGCUCAUUCAUCAAAGAGGUACAGAAGGGCGGUCCUGCUGACUUGGCUGGGCUAGAGGAUGAGGAUGUCAUCAUUGAAGUGAAUGGGGUGAAUGUGCUAGAUGAACCCUAUGAGAAGGUGGUGGAUAGAAUCCAGAGCAGUGGGAAGAAUGUCACACUUCUAGUCUGUGGAAAGAAGGCCUAUGAUUAUUUCCAAGCUAAGAAAAUCCCUAUUGUUUCCUCCCUGGCUGAUCCACUUGACACCCCUCCAGAUUCUAAAGAAGGAAUAGUGGUGGAGUCAAACCAUGACUCGCACAUGGCAAAAGAACGGCUCUACACAAUUGCUGUCAACUGCAUGCUGUGAAAGAAAGAAAUUCUAGUGAGUGACUCUACUCCCCGACUUAAGUCAUGCAACUCUAGAAUAGAUCAUCCCUCUUUCAUUACUCUACCAUUUGUAAAUUCUUUGUUUUCUUAUACACAGGCCCACAGUACAGCCUCACAUUCUUCUUCCAAUUCUGAAGAUACAGAGAUGUGAUGAAAACAAGUAAUAGCUUUGGCUGUUUAUUUGAUAGCUGUUUCUGGGUAUUUAAUAGGAAUCCUUUCUCAAGGAAUGAGUUGUGACCUGUUUACUGUCUCUUUAGAAGAAAAACUCCACUGGAAACCAUUCACCAUGUGUGAUUGUCUUCUGUUAUCAUUUGUCUUACAGGCGGCUAUUGCAGACGGCUAAUUUAUGCUUAACUUAGGAAGAGAUAAGGCAAGAGCUAGAUUUUUUUCAUGUGAUCUUUUCCAAGCUUCAACUUAACUUAACUACAUUUCUCUGUAUGAUGAUGUCUCUUACUUCUACAGGUUCCUUGAGCACCAAAGAUGAUUCAUAACUCUGUAUAGGUGACAGCUGCUUAUAAAAGCAUCUUAGCAGAUAAGCCUAUUAAAAUUGUGCUUUUGUAACAAUGUUGUGGUUGCUAGAAUAAAUACCAUUAACAAAUGCC